AACUCGGGGCGCGGGCGGCGGUGGGGCCCGGGCGCGGGCAGGGCUGGCCAUGGCGCGGGCGGCGGGCGCGCGGGGCCCUGCCGGGUGGUGCAGGAGGCGCGGGCGCUGCGGGCGGGGCACGCUCCUCGCCUUCGCCGCGUGGACCGCGGGCUGGGUGCUGGCGGCCGCGCUGCUGCUCCGCGCGCACCCGGGUGUCCUCUCCGAGCGCUGCACCGACGAGAAGAGCCGGCGCAUCCUGGCCGCGCUGUGCCAGGACUACCAGGGCGGCACGCUGGCCGGGGACCUCUGCGAGGACCUGUGUGUGGCGGGAGAGCUGCUGUUCCAACGCUGCCUGCACUACAACAGAGGCAAGAAGGUGCUGCAGGCCGACUGGCGCGGCCGGCCCGUGGUCCUCAAGUCCAAGGAGGAGGCCUUCUCCAGCUUCCCGCCCCUCAGCCUGUUGGAAGAGGAGGCAGGGGAGGGUGGCCAGGACAUGCCCGAGGCCGAACUCCUCCUGAUGGUGGCUGGGGAGGUCAAGAGCGCUCUGGGCCUGGAGUUGUCCAACAGCAGCCUGGGGCCGUGGUGGCCGGGCAGGCGGGGCCCACGCUGGCGGGGACAGCUGGCCAGCCUGUGGGCCCUGCUGCAGCAGGAGGAGUACGUCUACUUCAGCCUGCUGCAGGACCUGAGCCCACACGUGCUGCCCGUGCUGGGUUCCUGCGGCCACUUCUACGCGGUGGAGUUCCUGGCCGCGGGCAGCCCCCACCACAGGGCACUCUUCCCCCUGGACCGGGCCCCAGGUGCCCCUGGGGGUGGCCAGGCCAAGGCCAUCAGUGACAUCGCACUCAGCUUCUUGGACAUGGUGAACCAUUUUGACAGUGACUUUUCCCACCGCCUCCACCUCUGCGACAUCAAGCCGGAAAACUUUGCCAUCCGGAGCGACUUCACAGUGGUGGCUAUUGAUGUGGACAUGGCCUUUUUUGAACCUAAAAUGAGGGAAAUCCUUGAGCAAAACUGCACAGGAGAUGAAGACUGCAAUUUCUUUGACUGUUUUUCAAGAUGUGAUUUACGAGUCAACAAAUGCGGAGCGCAGCGCGUAAACAACAACCUGCAGGUCAUCUGUGACAAAAUAUUUCGCCAUUGGUUUUCCGCGCCUCUCAAGAGCUCUGCGGUCUCUUUCCAGCUUCAGCUGCAGUUACAGGAGGCGGUGCAGGAAUGUGCAGACCCUGGGGUCCCCAGUGGGAACACCCGGAGAGCAGCCUCCAGCGUGUUCUGGAAGCUUCGCCAACUCCUCCAAGCCACACUGAGGGAGCUGCAGGAGGCAGAGAAGUAGCCACUCUCUGGCCUUAAACAUGCUCACACAGGAAAAGUGACCUUGGCUGGAUUUCUUCUGCCAUUGUUUUAAAGAUGAGCCAUUUCCCCUGUGCUCUCUGGGGUGCCGUUCUGGUCUCCACAUUGUGGAGUGGCAAGUGCUGCUGCCAGAGACAGUGCUCCCUCGCUCUCGUCCCACCCUGGCCUCUGACCUGUCGCCUUGUGUAAAAUGAGAUGAGGGAGGAGGUACAGACCUCCCUUCAGGAGGGCUCUCGGUCAGAAGACACCAACCUGUGUGCACUUAUUCUCUGCAGAGAGCACUUGUACCUGGUUAUCCCAGCACGAGUUCCAGCUGUUCUUUCCUGUAAAUCGUUACCACGUUAAAAAGUGUGCGUGUGUGCAUACAAAUGAUGUGUAUGCCUGUGUCUGGGUGCAAAUGAGCAUGUGAGCAUGUGUGAGUGUGCCCAUGAGUGUCUGCAUGUGUGUGAGUGUGCACAGGUGAGUGUGCACAGGUGAGUGUGGUGUGCUCAUGAGGAGUAUGAGUAUGCCUGAGUGUGAAUAUGUAUGAGUGUGAAUGAGUGUGUGCACAUGAGUGCACGGGUGUCAGCAUGUGUAUAUAAGUGUGGGCAUGUGUAUGUGAUUGUGUGAGUGUGGGCAGGUGAGUGUGUUGGGGAUGUGGGUUAGGGUGGGGAGUGGUGCUUUCUCUAGUGUGUCCUCCGGAACAUCUUGCCUACCUAGCAAAGAAGUGUGACCAUUCUUUCGGAAUUAAAUACAAUAAAAAGAAAAUAAGCUGCAUCUUUAGGGAAGGGAAUUUGCAUUGGAGAGCGUGUGUAACGGCAGCUUAUAGUAUUUUUCAUUUUGUGGAAUCCACCAAGGUUAUGGAUGGGUUUUAGGGCGCCUCGUAUUGCAAUACACCUUCCCCUGGGCAGGGACUUGUAGGUUGGCUUGAUGCAGCAUUGUCUUCACCUUCAGAGAAAAUUUAAAGUAGAGCAAAUGCUGAGGUCUGCAUUGACUCCAGGCAGGACCAGAGACCAGCACCUUUCUUUUGAUGGAUUGAAGACCAAGUGAUAGGCAUCAAAUCCUAUGGUGGCAUGAUACGCUCAUCAGUGGUGAUCCCAAGGAGGCUUUUCCAGCAAAAUACAGGCAGGGGGACAGGCCAGGUGAAGCCAGUGAGCUUUCACUUAAAGGGACCUGGUUUCUACCCAUAACUGUGACCCACGAGUGCUCAACAAACCAACGGGUCACCCCUUUUCAGAAAUCCCAUGAAAAGGGAAAUCGAGAAAGAUGAGAGAAUCAGGAAGUCAUGUUGGCAGUUUACACAUUAAAGAAGACAAAUUAAUCGGACGUUGUGAAAGUCACAAACUGACACAUUCCAAAUGGUCUCUUAUCUUGGCCUGCAGCCCCUUUCUAAACCAGAGAAACGGGAAUGCCUUCUUCCAGACUUUGGGGUCACAUUUACUGACUCUGCCCUUCAGGGCACGCUGAGAAAUGGUGUGUGAGGGACUAGCAUGAUCAGAGGCCCCCAGCUCUAAAUUCUGCCUUCCCCAAAGACCUGUUGGAAGGCCCACUGCCAGCUGUUAUUCUUACCCAUCACCACUGGGGAUCUUCCAAAUGACACAGAGUUCCAUAGAGGGCCUCCUCAUCAUGGACAUGAAGACUCGCUUUGCAAUUGUAUUCUAGCAAGAAGGAAAAAACCCAUGUCAGUCACCCUGUGGCACGAGCAAAUUAAAACCAAAGUUCAACGGCCA